GCAGAGCUCGCCCGCCCGCCGGGGAGGCGAGGGAGCGCGGGGCUGGGCCCGGGGCCGCGGCGACAGGCAGCAGCCGCGGCGGGGACGCGGGGCGCGAGCGGGCGGCGCGGGACCGUCGGGGGCCGCCGGGGCCGGGCCGGGGUCGGGGCGCACGGCUACGCGGGCGCAGGUGGGCGAUCCCAUAGGGGCGGAGGGGGCACCCCGGCUCCGGAACCCGGGGCCCGGCAAGGCCAGGGGCGCCGCGGGGCCCCCGGGCGCAGGUGGUGAGUGCCCGGAGCGCAGGUGGAGGCGCGGCGGCAGCCCGCGGUGCUCAGGGUGACCCGGGAGCGGGUCUGGCUCAGGGGGCAGUGGGAGCCCGGGCUCGUCGGAGGGUGCAGCGCGGGGUCCCGCCGAGCCAUCCAGACGCAGGCCCCGCGGGGCGCACGGGAGGCCCCCGGGGACUGGCGCCCUGGCCCGGGCAUGAGGCGCGGCGGGGCCGGCAGGAGCCGGAGGAGGAGCCGCCGCCGCCGUUGACCCGGCCGCCGGCCGGGAGCUGGGAGAGAUGCGGAGCCCGGCCACCGGCGUCCCCCUCCCAACGCCGCCGCCGCCGCUGCUGCUGCUGUUGCUGCUGCUGCUGCCGCCGCCACUAUUGGGAGACCAAGUGGGGCCCUGUCGUUCCUUGGGGUCCAGGGGACGAGGCUCUUCGGGGGCCUGCGCCCCCAUGGGCUGGCUCUGUCCAUCCUCAGCGUCGAACCUCUGGCUCUACACCAGCCGCUGCAGGGAUGCGGGCACUGAGCUGACUGGCCACCUGGUACCCCACCACGAUGGCCUGAGGGUUUGGUGUCCAGAAUCCGAGGCCCAUAUUCCCCUACCACCAGCUCCUGAAGGCUGCCCCUGGAGCUGUCGCCUCCUGGGCAUUGGAGGCCACCUUUCCCCACAGGGCAAGCUCACACUGCCCGAGGAGCACCCGUGCUUAAAGGCUCCACGGCUCAGAUGCCAGUCCUGCAAGCUGGCACAGGCCCCCGGGCUCAGGGCAGGGGAAAGGUCACCAGAAGAGUCCCUGGGUGGGCGUCGGAAAAGGAAUGUAAAUACAGCCCCCCAGUUCCAGCCCCCCAGCUACCAGGCCACAGUGCCGGAGAACCAGCCAGCAGGCACCCCUGUUGCAUCCCUGAGGGCCAUCGACCCGGACGAGGGUGAGGCAGGUCGACUGGAGUACACCAUGGAUGCCCUCUUUGAUAGCCGCUCCAACCAGUUCUUCUCCCUGGACCCAGUCACUGGUGCAGUAACCACAGCCGAGGAGCUGGAUCGUGAGACCAAGAGCACCCACGUCUUCAGGGUCACGGCGCAGGACCACGGCAUGCCCCGACGAAGUGCCCUGGCUACACUCACCAUCUUGGUUACUGACACCAAUGACCAUGACCCUGUGUUCGAGCAGCAGGAGUACAAGGAGAGCCUCAGGGAGAACCUGGAGGUUGGCUAUGAGGUGCUCACUGUCAGGGCCACGGAUGGUGAUGCCCCUCCCAAUGCCAAUAUUCUGUACCGCCUGCUGGAGGGGUCUGGGGGCAGCCCCUCUGAAGUCUUUGAGAUCGACCCUCGCUCUGGGGUGAUCCGAACCCGUGGCCCUGUGGAUCGGGAAGAGGUGGAAUCCUACCAGCUGACGGUAGAGGCAAGUGACCAGGGUCGGGACCCGGGUCCUCGGAGUACCACAGCCGCUGUUUUCCUUUCUGUGGAGGAUGACAAUGAUAAUGCCCCCCAGUUUAGUGAGAAGCGCUAUGUGGUCCAGGUGAGGGAGGAUGUGACUCCAGGGGCCCCAGUACUCCGAGUCACAGCCUCGGAUCGAGACAAGGGGAGCAAUGCCGUGGUGCACUAUAGCAUCAUGAGUGGCAAUGCUCGGGGACAGUUUUAUCUGGAUGCCCAGACUGGAGCUCUGGAUGUGGUGAGCCCUCUUGACUAUGAGACGACCAAGGAGUACACCCUACGGGUGCGAGCACAGGAUGGUGGCCGUCCCCCACUCUCUAAUGUCUCUGGCUUGGUGACAGUACAGGUCCUGGAUAUCAACGACAAUGCCCCCAUCUUCGUCAGCACCCCUUUCCAGGCUACUGUCCUGGAGAGUGUCCCCUUAGGCUACCUGGUUCUCCAUGUCCAGGCUAUCGACGCUGAUGCUGGUGACAAUGCCCGCCUGGAAUACCGCCUUGCUGGGGUGGGACAUGACUUCCCCUUCACCAUCAACAAUGGCACAGGCUGGAUCUCUGUGGCUGCUGAACUGGACCGGGAGGAAGUUGAUUUCUACAGCUUUGGGGUAGAAGCUCGAGACCAUGGCACUCCAGCACUCACUGCCUCGGCCAGUGUCAGCGUGACUGUCCUGGAUGUCAACGACAACAAUCCAACCUUUACCCAACCAGAGUACACAGUGCGGCUCAAUGAGGAUGCAGCUGUGGGCACCAGCGUGGUGACGGUGUCAGCUGUGGACCGUGAUGCUCAUAGUGUCAUCACCUACCAGAUCACCAGUGGCAAUACUCGAAACCGCUUCUCCAUCACCAGCCAAAGUGGUGGUGGGCUGGUAUCCCUUGCCCUGCCACUGGACUACAAACUUGAGCGGCAGUAUGUGUUGGCUGUUACCGCCUCCGAUGGCACUCGGCAGGACACGGCACAGAUUGUGGUGAAUGUCACCGACGCCAACACCCAUCGUCCUGUCUUUCAGAGCUCCCACUAUACAGUGAAUGUUAAUGAGGACCGGCCGGCAGGCACCACGGUGGUGCUGAUCAGCGCCACGGAUGAGGACACAGGUGAGAAUGCCCGCAUCACCUACUUCAUGGAGGACAGCAUCCCCCAGUUCCGCAUCGAUGCAGACACGGGGGCUGUCACCACCCAGGCUGAGCUGGACUAUGAAGACCAAGUGUCUUACACCCUGGCCAUUACUGCUCGGGACAAUGGCAUUCCCCAGAAGUCCGACACCACCUACCUGGAGAUCCUGGUGAACGACGUGAAUGACAAUGCCCCUCAGUUCCUGCGAGACUCCUACCAGGGCAGUGUCUAUGAGGAUGUGCCACCCUUCACUAGCGUCCUGCAGAUCUCAGCCACUGAUCGUGAUUCUGGACUUAAUGGCAGGGUCUUCUACACCUUCCAAGGAGGCGACGAUGGAGACGGUGACUUUAUUGUUGAGUCCACGUCAGGCAUCGUGCGAACGCUACGGAGGCUGGAUCGAGAGAACGUGGCCCAGUAUGUCUUGCGGGCAUAUGCAGUGGACAAGGGGAUGCCCCCAGCCCGCACACCUAUGGAAGUGACAGUCACUGUGUUGGAUGUGAAUGACAAUCCCCCUGUCUUUGAGCAGGAUGAGUUUGAUGUGUUUGUGGAAGAGAACAGCCCCAUUGGGCUAGCCGUGGCCCGGGUCACAGCCACUGACCCCGAUGAAGGCACCAAUGCCCAGAUUAUGUACCAGAUUGUGGAGGGCAACAUCCCUGAGGUCUUUCAGCUGGACAUCUUCUCCGGGGAGCUGACAGCCCUGGUAGACUUAGACUACGAGGACCGGCCUGAGUACGUCCUGGUCAUCCAGGCCACGUCAGCUCCUCUGGUGAGCCGGGCUACAGUCCACGUCCGCCUCCUUGACCGCAAUGACAACCCACCAGUGCUGGGCAACUUUGAGAUCCUUUUCAACAACUAUGUCACCAAUCGCUCAAGCAGCUUCCCUGGGGGUGCCAUUGGCCGAGUACCUGCCCAUGACCCUGAUAUCUCAGAUAGUCUGACUUACAGCUUUGAGCGGGGAAAUGAACUCAGCCUGGUCCUGCUCAAUGCCUCCACGGGUGAGCUGAAGCUAAGCCGCGCACUGGACAACAACCGGCCUCUGGAGGCCAUCAUGAGCGUGCUGGUGUCAGACGGCGUACACAGCGUGACCGCCCAGUGCGCGCUGCGUGUGACCAUCAUCACCGAUGAGAUGCUCACCCACAGCAUCACGCUGCGCCUGGAGGACAUGUCACCCGAGCGCUUCCUGUCACCACUGCUAGGCCUCUUCAUCCAGGCGGUGGCCGCCACGCUGGCCACGCCACCGGACCACGUGGUGGUCUUCAACGUACAGCGGGACACCGACGCCCCCGGGGGCCACAUCCUCAACGUGAGCCUGUCGGUGGGCCAGCCGCCAGGGCCCGGGGGCGGGCCGCCCUUCCUGCCCUCUGAGGACCUGCAGGAGCGCCUAUACCUCAACCGCAGCCUGCUGACGGCCAUCUCGGCACAGCGCGUGCUGCCCUUCGACGACAACAUCUGCCUGCGGGAGCCCUGCGAGAACUACAUGCGCUGCGUGUCGGUGCUGCGCUUCGACUCCUCCGCGCCCUUCAUCGCCUCCUCCUCCGUGCUCUUCCGGCCCAUCCACCCCGUCGGAGGGCUGCGCUGCCGCUGCCCGCCCGGCUUCACGGGUGACUACUGCGAGACCGAGGUGGACCUCUGCUACUCGCGGCCCUGUGGCCCCCACGGGCGCUGCCGCAGCCGCGAGGGCGGCUACACCUGCCUCUGUCGUGAUGGCUACACGGGUGAGCACUGUGAGGUGAGUGCUCGCUCAGGCCGUUGCACCCCGGGUGUCUGCAAGAAUGGGGGCACCUGUGUCAACCUGCUGGUGGGCGGUUUCAAGUGCGAUUGCCCAUCUGGAGACUUCGAGAAGCCCUACUGCCAGGUGACCACGCGCAGCUUCCCCGCCCACUCCUUCAUCACCUUUCGCGGCCUGCGCCAGCGUUUCCACUUCACCCUGGCCCUCUCGUUUGCCACAAAGGAGCGCGACGGGUUGCUGUUGUACAAUGGGCGUUUCAAUGAGAAGCAUGACUUUGUGGCCCUCGAGGUGAUCCAGGAGCAGGUCCAGCUCACCUUCUCUGCAGGGGAGUCAACCACCACGGUGUCCCCAUUCGUGCCCGGAGGAGUCAGUGAUGGCCAGUGGCAUACGGUGCAGCUGAAAUACUACAAUAAGCCACUGUUGGGUCAGACAGGGCUCCCACAGGGCCCAUCAGAGCAGAAGGUGGCUGUGGUGACCGUGGAUGGCUGUGACACAGGAGUGGCCUUGCGCUUCGGAUCUGUCCUGGGCAACUACUCCUGUGCUGCCCAGGGCACCCAGGGUGGCAGCAAGAAGUCUCUGGAUCUGACGGGGCCCCUGCUACUAGGCGGGGUGCCUGACCUGCCCGAGAGCUUCCCAGUCCGAAUGCGGCAGUUCGUGGGCUGCAUGCGGAACCUGCAGGUGGACAGCCGGCACAUAGACAUGGCUGACUUCAUUGCCAACAAUGGCACCGUGCCUGGCUGCCCUGCCAAGAAGAACGUGUGUGACAGCAACACUUGCCACAAUGGGGGCACUUGCGUGAACCAGUGGGACGCGUUCAGCUGCGAGUGCCCCCUGGGCUUUGGGGGCAAGAGCUGCGCCCAGGAAAUGGCCAAUCCACAGCACUUCCUGGGCAGCAGCCUGGUGGCCUGGCAUGGCCUCUCGCUGCCCAUCUCCCAACCCUGGUACCUCAGCCUCAUGUUCCGCACGCGCCAGGCCGACGGUGUCCUGCUGCAGGCCAUCACCAGGGGGCGCAGCACCAUCACCCUACAGCUACGAGAGGGCCACGUGAUGCUGAGCGUGGAGGGCACAGGGCUUCAGGCCUCCUCUCUCCGUCUGGAGCCAGGCCGGGCCAAUGACGGUGACUGGCACCAUGCACAGCUGGCACUGGGAGCCAGCGGGGGGCCCGGCCAUGCCAUUCUGUCCUUCGAUUAUGGGCAGCAGAGAGCAGAGGGCAACCUGGGCCCCCGGCUGCAUGGUCUGCACCUGAGCAACAUAACAGUGGGCGGAAUACCUGGGCCAGCCGGCGGUGUGGCCCGUGGCUUUCGGGGCUGUUUGCAGGGUGUGCGGGUGAGCGAUACGCCGGAGGGGGUUAACAGCCUGGAUCCCAGCCAUGGGGAGAGCAUCAACGUGGAGCAAGGCUGUAGCCUGCCUGACCCUUGUGACUCAAACCCGUGUCCUGCUAACAGCUAUUGCAGCAACGACUGGGACAGCUAUUCCUGCAGCUGUGAUCCAGGUUACUAUGGUGACAACUGUACUAAUGUGUGUGACCUGAACCCGUGUGAGCACCAGUCUGUGUGUACCCGCAAGCCCAGUGCCCCCCAUGGCUAUACCUGCGAGUGUCCCCCAAAUUACCUUGGGCCAUACUGUGAGACCAGGAUUGACCAGCCUUGUCCCCGUGGCUGGUGGGGACAUCCCACAUGUGGCCCAUGCAACUGUGAUGUCAGCAAAGGCUUUGACCCAGACUGCAACAAGACAAGCGGCGAGUGCCACUGCAAGGAGAACCACUACCGGCCCCCAGGCAGCCCCACCUGCCUCUUGUGUGACUGCUACCCCACAGGCUCCUUGUCCAGAGUCUGUGACCCUGAGGAUGGCCAGUGUCCAUGCAAGCCAGGUGUCAUCGGGCGUCAGUGUGACCGCUGUGACAACCCUUUUGCUGAGGUCACCACCAAUGGCUGUGAAGUGAAUUAUGACAGCUGCCCACGAGCGAUUGAGGCUGGGAUCUGGUGGCCCCGUACCCGCUUCGGGCUGCCUGCUGCUGCUCCCUGUCCCAAAGGCUCCUUUGGGACUGCUGUGCGCCACUGUGAUGAGCACAGGGGGUGGCUCCCCCCAAACCUCUUCAACUGCACGUCCAUCACCUUCUCAGAACUGAAGGGCUUCGCUGAGCGGCUACAGCGGAAUGAGUCAGGCCUAGACUCAGGGCGCUCCCAGCAGCUAGCCCUGCUCCUGCGCAACGCCACGCAGCACACAGCUGGCUACUUCGGCAGCGACGUCAAGGUGGCCUACCAGCUGGCCACGCGGCUGCUGGCCCACGAGAGCACCCAGCGGGGCUUUGGGCUGUCUGCCACACAGGACGUGCACUUCACUGAGAAUCUGCUGCGGGUGGGCAGCGCCCUCCUGGACACAGCCAACAAGCGGCACUGGGAGCUGAUCCAGCAGACAGAGGGUGGCACCGCCUGGCUGCUCCAGCACUAUGAGGCCUACGCCAGUGCCCUGGCCCAGAACAUGCGGCACACCUACCUAAGCCCCUUCACCAUCGUCACGCCCAACAUUGUCAUCUCCGUAGUGCGCUUGGACAAAGGGAACUUUGCUGGGGCCAAGCUGCCCCGCUACGAGGCCCUGCGUGGGGAGCAGCCCCCGGACCUUGAGACAACAGUCAUUCUGCCUGAGUCUGUCUUCAGAGAGACGCCCCCCGUGGUCAGGCCCGCAGGCCCCGGAGAGGCCCAGGAGCCAGAGGAGCUGGCACGGCGACAGCGACGGCACCCGGAGCUGAGCCAGGGUGAGGCUGUGGCCAGCGUCAUCAUCUACCGCACCCUGGCCGGGCUACUGCCUCAUAACUAUGACCCUGACAAGCGCAGCUUGAGAGUCCCCAAACGCCCGAUCAUCAACACACCCGUGGUGAGCAUCAGCGUCCAUGAUGAUGAGGAGCUUCUGCCCCGGGCCCUGGACAAACCCGUCACGGUGCAGUUCCGCCUGCUGGAGACAGAGGAGCGGACCAAGCCCAUCUGUGUCUUCUGGAACCAUUCAAUCCUGGUCAGUGGCACAGGUGGCUGGUCGGCCAGAGGCUGUGAAGUCGUCUUCCGCAAUGAGAGCCACGUCAGCUGCCAGUGCAACCACAUGACGAGCUUCGCUGUGCUCAUGGACGUUUCUCGGCGGGAGAAUGGGGAGAUCCUGCCACUGAAGACACUGACAUACGUGGCUCUAGGUGUCACCUUGGCUGCCCUUCUGCUCACCUUCUUCUUCCUCACUCUCUUGCGUAUCCUGCGCUCCAACCAACACGGCAUCCGACGUAACCUGACAGCUGCCCUGGGCCUGGCUCAGCUGGUCUUCCUCCUGGGAAUCAACCAGGCUGACCUCCCUUUUGCCUGCACAGUCAUUGCCAUCCUGCUGCACUUCCUGUACCUCUGCACCUUUUCCUGGGCUCUGCUGGAGGCCUUGCACCUGUACCGGGCACUCACUGAGGUGCGCGAUGUCAACACCGGCCCCAUGCGCUUCUACUACAUGCUGGGCUGGGGCGUGCCUGCCUUCAUCACAGGGCUAGCCGUGGGCCUGGACCCCGAGGGCUACGGGAACCCUGACUUCUGCUGGCUCUCCAUCUAUGACACGCUCAUCUGGAGUUUUGCUGGCCCGGUGGCCUUUGCCGUCUCGAUGAGUGUCUUCCUGUACAUCCUGGCGGCCCGGGCCUCCUGUGCUGCCCAGCGGCAGGGCUUUGAGAAGAAAGGUCCUGUCUCGGGCCUGCAGCCCUCCUUCGCCGUCCUCCUGCUGCUGAGCGCCACGUGGCUGCUGGCACUGCUCUCUGUCAACAGCGACACCCUCCUCUUCCACUACCUCUUUGCUACCUGCAAUUGCAUCCAGGGCCCCUUCAUCUUCCUCUCCUAUGUGGUGCUUAGCAAGGAGGUCCGGAAAGCACUCAAGCUUGCCUGCAGCCGCAAGCCCAGCCCUGACCCUGCUCUGACCACCAAGUCCACCCUGACCUCGUCCUACAACUGCCCCAGCCCCUACGCAGAUGGGCGGCUGUACCAGCCCUACGGAGACUCGGCCGGCUCUCUGCACAGCACCAGUCGCUCGGGCAAGAGUCAGCCCAGCUACAUCCCCUUCUUGCUGAGGGAGGAGUCCGCACUGAACCCUGGCCAAGGGCCCCCUGGCCUGGGGGAUCCAGGCAGCCUGUUCCUGGAAGGUCAAGACCAGCAGCAUGAUCCUGACACGGACUCCGACAGUGACCUGUCCUUAGAAGACGACCAGAGUGGCUCCUAUGCCUCUACCCACUCAUCAGACAGUGAGGAGGAAGAAGAGGAGGAGGAAGAGGAGGCCGCCUUCCCUGGAGAGCAGGGCUGGGAUAGCCUGCUGGGGCCUGGAGCAGAGAGACUGCCCCUGCACAGUACUCCCAAGGAUGGGGGCCCAGGGCCUGGCAAGGCCCCCUGGCCAGGAGACUUUGGGACCACAGCAAAAGAGAGUAGUGGCAACGGGGCCCCUGAGGAGCGGCUGCGGGAGAAUGGAGAUGCCCUGUCUCGAGAGGGGUCCCUAGGCCCCCUUCCAGGCUCUUCUGCCCAGCCUCACAAAGGCAUCCUUAAGAAGAAGUGUCUGCCCACCAUCAGCGAGAAGAGCAGCCUCCUGCGGCUCCCCCUGGAGCAAUGCACAGGGUCUUCCCGGGGCUCCUCCGCUAGUGAGGGCAGCCGGGGAGGCCCCCCUCCCCGCCCACCGCCCCGGCAGAGCCUCCAGGAGCAGCUGAACGGGGUCAUGCCCAUCGCCAUGAGCAUCAAGGCAGGCACGGUGGAUGAGGACUCGUCAGGCUCCGAAUUUCUCUUCUUUAACUUCCUGCAUUAACCCUGGGCCGUGGUUCCUACGCCCGAGGCUCCCUUCCCUUCCCCAGCCGCACUCAUGCCCUGCUCCUGUCUUGUGCUUUAUCCUGCCCCGCUCCCCAUCGCCUGCCCGCAGCAGCGACGAAACGUCCAUCUGAGGAGCCUGGGCCUUGCCGGGAGGGGUACUCACCCCACCUAAGGCCAUCUAGUGCCAACUCCCCCCCCACCAUUCCCCUCACUGCACUUUGGACCCCUGGGGCCAACAUCUCCAAGACAAAGUUUUUCAGAAAAGAGGAAAAAAAGAAUUUAAAAAAGGAUCUCCACUCUUCAUGACUUCAGGGAUUCAUUUUUUUUAUACGCUGGAAAUUGACUCCCCUUUCCCUUCCCAAAGAGGAUAGGACCUCCCAGGAUGCUUCCCAGCCUCUCCUCAGUUUCCCAUCUGCUGUGCCUCUGGGAGGAGAGGGACUCCUGGGGGGCCUGCCCCUCAUACGCCAUCACCAAAAGGAAAGGACAAAGCCACACGCAGCCAGGGCUUCACACCCUUCAGGCUGCACCCGGGCAGGCCUCAGAACGGUGAGGGGCCAGGGCAAAGGGUGUGCCUCGUCCUGCCCGCACUGCCUCUCCCAGGAACUGGAAAAGCCCUGUCCGGUGAGGGGGCAGAAGGACUCAGCGCCCCUGGACCCCCAAAUGCUGCAUGAACACAUUUUCAGGGGAGCCUGUGCCCCCAGGCGGGGGUCGGGCAGCCCCAGCCCCUCUCCUUUUCCUGGACUCUGGCCGUGCGCGGCAGCCCAGGUGUUUGCUCAGUUGCUGACCCAAAAGUGCUUCAUUUUUCGUGCCCGCCCCGCGCCCCGGGCAGGCCAGUCAUGUGUUAAGUUGCGCUUCUUUGCUGUGAUGUGGGUGGGGGAGGAAGAGUAAACACAGUGCUGGCUCGGCUGCCCUGAGGGUGCUCAAUCAAGCACAGGUUUCAAGUCUGGGUUCUGGUGUCCACUCACCCACCCCACCCCCCAAAAUCAGACAAAUGCUACUUUGUCUAACCUGCUGUGGCCUCUGAGACAUGUUCUAUUUUUAACCCCUUCUUGGAAUUGGCUCUCUUCUUCAAAGGACCAGGUCCUGUUCCUCUUUCUCCCCGACUCCACCCCAGCUCCCUGUGAAGAGAGAGUUAAUAUAUUUGUUUUAUUUAUUUGCUUUUUGUGUUGGGAUGGGUUCGUGUCCAGUCCCGGGGGUCUGAUAUGGCCAUCACAGGCUGGGUGUUCCCAGCAGCCCUGGCUUGGGGGCUUGACGCCCUUCCCCUUGCCCCAGGCCAUCAUCUCCCCACCUCUCCUCCCCUCUCCUCAGUUUUGCCGACUGCUUUUCAUCUGAGUCACCAUUUACUCCAAGCAUGUAUUCCAGACUUGUCACUGACUUUCCUUCUGGAGCAGGUGGCUAGAAAAAGAGGCUGUGGGCAGGAAAGAAAGGCUCCUGUUUCUCAUUUGUGAGGCCAGCCUCUGGCUUUUCUGCCGUGGAUUCUCCCCCGUCUUCUCCCCUCAGCAAUUCCUGCAAAGGGUUAAAAAUUUAACUGGUUUUUACUACUGAUGACUUGAUUUAAAAAAAAUACAAAGAUGCUGGAUGCUAACUUGGUACUAACCAUCAGAUUGUACAGUUUGGUUGUUGCUGUAAAUAGGGUAGCGUUUUGUUGUUGUUGUUUUUUCAUGCCCCAUACUACUGAAUAAACUAGUUCUGUGCGGGUA